AGAGCAGGGCCUGACAUCUCCCCAGAACAGACGUUUGAACAGAGCAGGCUUCUGAGGUCUCCAAAAUGCCUGUCCCAGCCUCCUGGCCCCAUCCUCCUGGUCCUUUCCUGCUUCUGACUCUACUGCUGGGACUUACAGAAGUGGCAGGUGAGGAGGAGCUACAGAUGAUUCAGCCUGAGAAGCUCCUGUUGGUCACAGUUGGAAAGACAGCCACUCUGCACUGCACUGUGACCUCCCUGCUUCCCGUGGGACCCGUCCUGUGGUUCAGAGGAGUUGGACCAGGCCGGGAAUUAAUCUACAAUCAAAAAGAAGGCCACUUCCCCAGGGUAACAACAGUUUCAGACCUCACAAAGAGAAACAACAUGGACUUUUCCAUCCGCAUCAGUAGCAUCACCCCAGCAGAUGUCGGCACAUACUACUGUGUGAAGUUUCGAAAAGGGAGCCCUGAGAACGUGGAGUUUAAGUCUGGACCAGGCACUGAGAUGGCUUUGGGUGCCAAACCCUCUGCCCCCGUGGUAUUGGGCCCUGCGGCGAGGACCACACCUGAGCAUACAGUGAGUUUCACCUGUGAGUCCCAUGGCUUCUCUCCCAGAGACAUCACCCUGAAAUGGUUCAAAAAUGGGAAUGAGCUCUCAGACUUCCAGACCAACGUGGACCCCACAGGACAGAGUGUGGCCUACAGCAUCCGCAGCACAGCCAGGGUGGUACUGGACCCCUGGGACGUUCGCUCUCAGGUCAUCUGCGAGGUGGCCCAUGUCACCUUGCAGGGGGACCCUCUUCGUGGGACUGCCAACUUGUCUGAGGCCAUCCGAGUUCCACCCACCUUGGAGGUUACUCAACAGCCCAUGAGGGUGGGGAACCAGGUAAACGUCACCUGCCAGGUGAGGAAGUUCUACCCCCAGAGCCUACAGCUGACCUGGUCGGAGAAUGGAAACGUGUGCCAGAGAGAAACAGCCUCGACCCUUACAGAGAACAAGGAUGGUACCUACAACUGGACAAGCUGGUUCCUGGUGAACAUAUCUGACCAAAGGGAUGAUGUGGUCCUCACCUGCCAGGUGAAGCAUGAUGGGCAGCUGGCGGUCAGCAAACGCCUUGCCCUAGAGGUCACAGUCCACCAGAAGGACCAGAGCUCAGAUGCUACCCCUGGCCCGGCAUCAUCCCUUACUGCGCUGCUCCUCAUAGCUGUCCUCCUGGGCCCCAUCUACGUCCCCUGGAAGCAGAAGACCUGACUCUCCUUCCUUCCUCCCCUGCCACGUGGGACCCUCAUCUCUGCUGCCUCCUUCCUUUCCUGAGAGGCUCAGCUUGAGAGAAUGAGCCAGUGAGAAGCUUCUCUAGACUUGGCUCCAAACAUCUCCCCUCCCAAGACAUCUGCCUGCCCACAGGCUCCUGUUGCUCCUUCACACAGACCUGGAUGCCCCAGAGCAAGGUCUUCAUUCAUGGUCCUGAGCAGGUGCCAUGGGAUUGGGCUCUGGGCACUGACUUAACGGCACCUCCCUAGAAGGCGAGAAACAUGCCAAAUCUAAACACACCAGGACUCCCAUCCAUCGCCUUGAGACUGACCGUAAACCACAGACGCUCUCCAGGUUCUCAAGAGUUAUCCUGCCUUCCAGAUUCCUGCCUAUCCCAACUCCCCAGCCUUGUUGAGGUUCUCUAUUGCCUCUUGAAUACAAAUGCACUCCCAAAGUGGUUUUAAGAAAAUAAAAAGAUUAUCCUUCC